GCCGGGACUGCGGGUGCUCGGCCGGAGCGCUCCAGCCGCUGGUCCCCGGGAGACCCUGUGCCCCUAAAUCGCGGUCCACUGCGCGCGUCAGGUUUCUAGAAGCAGGGUAGAACAGACGGCAGACACCUAGCCCAGGCUGGUGUUGUUACUAAACAAUGGCAGCUGGUGAGCCAAGGGUGACCAGGGCCCUGAACUCGGUGGCCCAGCUUUGAGGGAAGCAAAAUUGUUCUCAAUUGUGGAAGAGGAGAAUUUGGACAGCAGAACAAAAAAGGAAGACAGCCUCUUGGAGCAGAUACAUUUGUCACAGGAAGCCACAUCAAACCCUGGGGCCUUUGCUGGGCCUCUCCAUCUGCCCAGUUACUGGGAGGUAGAUAGCCCCAGGAAGGAAUCCAGUCAGGCCUGGGCACCAGGCCAGGAGUGGAUAAAGCUAGAAAGAGACACCACAGAAGAGAAGAUGUUUGAACAGCUGAAGCCAAUCGAACCUGUACAGAAGACGCUCCCAUGGGUGGGCGAGGUAGCUGCCACCCUGCAGGAAGCCAUGAAGAGAGAUUGCUGGAGGGAGGCACGGGUGAAGAAGAAGCCAGUCACCUUUGAGGAUGUGGCAGUGAAUUUCACCCAGGAAGAGUGGGACUGUCUAGAUGCCAGCCAGAGGGUCCUUUACCAGGAUGUUAUGUCGGAAACCUUUAAGAAUCUAACAUCUGUGGCCAGAAUCUUUCUGCAUAAGCCAGAGCUAAUCACCAAGCUUGAGCAAGAAGAGGAACAGUGGAGAGAGUUUGUCCAUCUCCCAAACACAGAAGGCCUUUCAGAAGGCAAGAAGAAAGAGCUUCGAGAACAACAUCCCAGUCUGAGAGAUGAGGGGACUAGUGAUGACAAGGUCUUCCUUGCAUGCAGAGGGGCCGGCCAGUGCCCCCUAUCUGCCCCAGCUGGGACUAUGGACAGGACCCGGGUGCUUCAAGCAUCCCAGGCUGGGCCACCCUUUUUUUGCUACACCUGUGGCAAAUGUUUCAGCAGGCGCUCCUACCUCUAUAGCCACCAGUUUGUUCACAAUCCCAAGCUGACUAACAGCUGCAGUCAGUGUGGGAAGUUGUUUCGGAGCCCCAAGUCCCUCAGCUAUCACAGACGCAUGCAUCUUGGGGAGAGGCCCUUCUGUUGCACGCUCUGUGACAAGACCUACUGUGAUGCUUCUGGACUAAGUCGUCACCGCCGCGUCCAUCUGGGUUACCGGCCCCAUUCAUGCUCUGUGUGUGGGAAGAGCUUCCGGGACCAGUCUGAGCUCAAACGCCACCAGAAGAUACACCAAAACCAGGAGCCAGUGGAUGGAAACCAGGAGUGUACUUUGAGGAUUCCAGGCACCCAGGCUGAAUUCCAGACACCCAUCGCCAGAAGCCAGAGGUCCAUCCAGGGGCUUUUGGAUGUGAACCAUGCACCAGUGGCCAGGUCCCAGGAACCCAUAUUUAGAACUGAGGGUCCUAUGGCCCAGAACCAGGCAUCUGUACUUAAGAACCAAGCACCUGUGACCAGGACCCAGGCACCCAUCACUGGAACCCUCUGUCAGGAUGCCAGAUCCAACUCUCAUCCAGUGAAGCCCUCAAGACUCAAUGUCUUCUGUUGCCCCCAUUGUUCUUUGACUUUUAGCAAGAAAUCCUAUCUCUCCAGACACCAGAAGGCCCACCUCACAGAGCCGCCCAACUACUGCUUCCAUUGCAGCAAGUCUUUCAGCUCAUUUUCCAGGCUGGUCAGACACCAGCAGACCCACUGGAAGCAGAAGAGCUACCUUUGCCCUAUCUGUGACCUCUCCUUUGGGGAGAAAGAGGGCCUUAUGGAUCACUGGAGGGGCUAUAAAGGCAAGGACCUGUGCCAGAGCAGCCACCAUAAAUGCCGGGUGAUCCUGGGCCAGUGGCUUGGCUUCUCUCAUGAUGUCCCCACUAUGGCUGGGGAGGAAUGGAAGCAUGGAGGUGAUCAAUCUCCCCCCAGGAUCCAUACCCCCAGGAGAAGAGGCCUAAGAGAGAAGGCCUGCAAAGGAGACAAAACAAAGGAGGCAGUGAGCAUCUUGAAACAUAAAUAAAUGGCCUUUCUGACUGA